AGUUACUCGCUGAUCUCCGUGGAGUCCAGGUCUUCUGCCCAAGAUGAAUUUGGAGGGCACUUCAGGUGGCAUACUUCAAAAAGAAUUCUGGAGAAACAGAAUUCAGUAUAACCAGAGUCAAAAGGAUAUCCUCCAAUCAUGGUUUCAACAUGACCCUUUCCCUGAUAAAGCUGCCAGAGAACAACUGGCCAAAGAAAUUGGGGUUCCAGAAUCUAAUAUUCAGGUUUGGUUUAAAAAUUACAGAGUAAAACAGAGAAAACUGGAUUAUAAGUGCUUCUCAGAAAAAGAUCAAACCCAGGGGCAUGACCAGUCCCAGCAUCUGACUCAAGAAUACUUACCUAAAGAAGCCCGACAAAAACAGACAUUCAUCACAUGGACUCAAAAAAACAGGCUAGUGCAAGCCUUUGAGAGGAACCCAUUCCCUGAUAUUGCUACCAGAAAAAAACUGGCUGAACAAACAGGCCUGCAGGAAUCAAGAAUUCAAAUGUGGUUUCAGAAACAAAGAUCUCUGUACCUCAAGAAGAGCAGAAUGGAGCCCAUGAAUUUAUUGGUAGACGACCCAAAUGAGAGACCAGAUGCAACUGUUGGGUGGCAUCCAAUCAACCUGUUCCUCCCCACAGACAGCUCUCAUUAUUUUUCUUGCUCACAUUCUUCCAGCGGGCAUGAAACUCUUCCACCUGUUCUUCCUUCAACCCAGGCUCCUUGGGAUCCCUUCAGGUUCCAUGUGAGCCAAGGACCAAAUGUCAUGAUCAUGCAGCCCACACAGGCUGUGCAGGAAGGAGAGAAGUCUGAUCAGCCUCUGAUAAUUCCGAAUCACCUCCUGACACUGCCAAUUCUGACAAAGGACUUAGAUACUCCGACUCCCUUCUGGCUCCAAUACCAAGAAGAACACCAAAAUCACAAAGAACACUCUGGCUCGGGAGUACCACAGGUCAAGAGCCAUUCUCAGCCUGAACCUGAGCACAGGGAGCAACAACCUCUAAAUCUGGGUCAGUUUGACAUAUCGAACAUUUUGCAAAGGUGGGACGAGAUCUGCCAGGCUCUGCUUGCUGAAUGGGACCCUCUCAAAGGGACACACUGAGACAGACUUGUGGCAGCAGUAGGCACACUCAGCUGA